AGAGCCGGAGCCCGCAACCCGCUCAGGCGGCGACGGAGCCAUGUCGCCGCUGCUGGGGCUCCGGUCCGAGCUGCAGGACACCUGCACCUCGCUGGGACUGAUGCUGUCGGUGGUGCUGCUCAUGGGGCUGGCCCGCGUAGUCGCCCGGCAGCAGCUGCACAGGCCGGUGGCCCACGCCUUCGUCCUGGAGUUUCUAGCCACCUUCCAGCUCUGCUGCUGCACCCACGAGCUGCAACUGCUGAGCGAACAGCACCCCGCGCACCCCACCUGGACGCUGACGCUCGUCUACUUCUUCUCGCUUGUGCAUGGCCUGACUCUGGUGGGCACGUCCAGCAACCCGUGCGGCGUGAUGAUGCAGAUGAUGCUGGGGGGCAUGUCCCCCGAGACGGGUGCGGUGAGGCUAUUGGCUCAGCUGGUUAGUGCCCUGUGCAGCAGGUACUGCACAAGCGCCUUGUGGAGCUUGGGUCUGACCCAGUAUCACGUCAGCGAGAGGAGCUUCGCUUGCAAGAAUCCCAUCCGAGUCGACUUGCUCAAAGCGGUCAUCACAGAGGCCGUCUGCUCCUUUCUCUUCCACAGCGCUCUGCUGCACUUCCAGGAAGUCCGAACCAAGCUUCGUAUCCACCUGCUGGCUGCACUCAUCACCUUUUUGGUCUAUGCAGGAGGAAGUCUAACAGGAGCUGUAUUUAAUCCAGCUUUGGCACUUUCGCUACAUUUCAUGUGUUUUGAUGAAGCAUUCCCUCAGUUUUUUAUAGUAUACUGGCUGGCUCCUUCUUUAGGUAUAUUGUUGAUGAUUUUGAUGUUCAGCUUUUUCCUUCCAUGGCUGCAUAACAACCAUACAAUUAAUAAAAAGGAAUAACUGUUCCAAAGACUCAGACUAACAUACAGGACAGUCCAGCUGGAUGUGAUAAAGAUUUUAUCACCUCAUAUGGAAAACACCGGCUGCACUGGAUUCAUCAGUGUUAACUUCCUUUGAGGAAGCUGCCUUAUAGUUUUCAUCACUGGGACUUUAAAAAAAAAUUACUGUGAAAAUGAGGUAUUCUGUACUUCUCAGUUAAGACUUGUUCUUUGAGUGAUGUAUUAAAUGCUGCUAGAAAAGCCUCAUUACAUUAAAUAUAAAUCAAUCUUAAAUGAUAAUUGUUAACUUUGAUGAAAAACGAGUACAGGAUGAGAAGGGAAGUAAAGGUGAUAGUAAGAUCAACGAAUUUGUGUAUCAAGUGUCACCCAAAUGAACAGAAUUUUUAACUAUAAAAGUACAAGGCGUCAACUUACAGAACUGGGGAGAGGAUACUUUCAGCCACCACCUCACAAAAUGAUACCAUCAAGCAGUGUCAUCUUUCAACAGGAAAGUUGCUUUUAGAAGUAGAAUAUAUAUUCACUCACAUGCAAGCGAUUUCCUACAUUUUAAGUACAUUAAAAUCUAAUACCUAAAAUAGUUUCUCUAAAUAGACAAUCUCACUAGCUCCAGCCAAGUGGUUAUUCUUUAAUAGAAUAUAAUAAAACAAAACACCCAUACAAAGUCAGGAUUUAAGCUUUUCACAUUCUCCUUUGAACCAACAGCUAGCUACCUUAUGAAGUAGGGAGGGCAUGUAUUUUUAAUCUCCAUUUUACAGAUAAGGAAACUAAGCCUAGAUGGGUUUGCUGCCCUGGCUUAGAUCACAUAGAGCCAAAUACCAUCUCUAGUCUUCAACUUCAAUCCAAAAAUUCUUCUCGGUCACGAUUAUGACUAAAGGGAAAUCAAGGGUUCAUAGAAACAUUAAAUACUUUAUAAUAACGUUAAAACUUGUUUAGAAAUUAACUAGUAUUUUUUGAGGUUUAAAGAACCUUCCAGUUUUACU